AGAGCUCUGUGAACCUCUUCUGGUUGUGAGUGCUGCCUGAUUCGUGAGUUGUUUGUUGCUCAGACAGUCCCUGACUCACAAUGGUUUGACUUAACCAUUUUUCAACUUUAUAAUGGUGCAGAGACAAUACACAGUCAGUAUGCUCAACUUUCGGUGUGGUUACACCCAAGUAAACACAUCAUCGUCAUAAAUUGAGAAACUUGUUCUUGAAGUCAUUACUUACUGAGAAAAGAAUCACUAUCCAAGAUGAAAAAUCAGGAACUUCAACAACAGCUCCUUUAUUUCCAUUUCUACUUCUGUUGGAAAUACCAAAAUAUUUGCAGACUGGAUCCAAAUCAGGAGCCCAGAUGAACUUAAAGAAGCGAGCAUGGGAUUCUUAGUUUUUCAAGAUCCGUACACACGAAGCCUUUAAUCAGCAUCAACUCCAGUGUCCGUUUUCUCUGGUUUUGUGAAGACUGCACAAAACUCUCAUGAUGGAGAACCAAAGGACUUAGUUACCUGUUUCAGUGUCAUCUAAAGUCAACUGAAAAGUGAAGCAGGCAGUAAUACAGCCAUGGAAAGAAAUUCAAGUUUAUGGAAGAACCUAAUAGAUGAACACCCAGUCUGCACAACCUGGAAGCAAGAGGCCGAAGGAGCCAUUUAUCAUCUUGCCAGUAUUUUAUUUGUAGUAGGUUUCAUGGGUGGCAGUGGAUUCUUCGGGCUCCUUUAUGUCUUCAGUUUGCUGGGGUUGGGUUUUCUCUGUUCUGCUGUCUGGGCUUGGGUAGAUGUCUGUGCAGCUGACAUAUUUUCCUGGAAUUUUGUACUGUUUGUCAUCUGCUUCAUGCAAUUUGUUCAUAUUGCAUAUCAAGUUCGCAGCAUAACCUUUGCCCGAGAAUUCCAAGUGUUGUACAGCUCCCUUUUCCAGCCCCUGGGGAUCUCUUUGCCUGUCUUCAGAACGAUUGCUUUGAGCUCUGAAGUGGUUACUUUGGAAAAGGAACACUGUUAUGCCAUGCAGGGGAAAACUUCCAUUGAUAAACUCUCCUUGCUUGUUUCAGGAAGGAUCAGAGUGACAGUUGAUGGCGAAUUUCUGCAUUACAUUUUCCCCCUUCAGUUCCUGGAUUCUCCUGAGUGGGAUUCACUGAGACCCACAGAGGAAGGCAUUUUUCAGGUAACCCUCACUGCAGAAACUGAUUGUCGAUAUGUGUCUUGGAGGAGAAAGAAAUUAUAUCUGCUCUUUGCUCAGCAUCGCUACAUCUCCCGCCUUUUUUCAGUGCUAAUUGGCAGUGACAUUGCAGAUAAACUCUAUGCCUUGAAUGACAGGGUAUAUAUAGGAAAAAGAUAUCACUAUGAUAUUCGGCUACCCAACUUCUAUCAAAUGUCAACUCCAGAAAUACGCAGAUCACCCCUGACACAACAUUUUCAGAAUUCCAGACGAUACUGUGAUAAAUGACAUCAAAGUCUGAAAUUUAUAAGUAUAAAAAAAGACUCUCUCUUCAUCAUUCCCCAGUGAAAUAGCAAAAUACAAAAAAAGAGCUCCCUAAUGUUUUUAUAAAUCAAAUUCAGAAGCGAGAUGCCAUUGCCAACUGUUUUAUUCCUUUCAACAACUGCAUUGUGAAUAAACUUUACAAAUUUUUCUUGUAUUUCUCAUUGUUAUAAUUGGGGAGGGGGUGGAUAACUAUGGGCAGUUUGCCCUUUUCUGCAUCAAAACUGGGAGAAUGAAAUUCCACUUUCUCAAUUCUUUUCUCACAUUUACUCAAAUGCAUUGUCUUGCCCUAUAGACUCAGGAGUUGCUUCUCAAGAAAGAGCCAGCAAGUAUUCUCAGCCUGAGGGUGGGUUGCUACUGUCCACAUAGGCAUUUCCGGAAUUCACUUUUUUGCUACAACCUCCAGUGAAAGCAAUUAUUUAUUUUAAAUGUGCAGUUACUUGAUGCGACUAAAAAGUAGAAUAAAUGCAAGAGAUAAUAAUAUGUGAAUCUUGAAGCCUAUUUUAUUGCUACAAAUAAAAUAACAUUUAAAAAGAA